GGGAUGGGCCCUGGGAAGGAGAAAAGCCGCACCCUCAGCCCUGCAGCCCUCCAGCAAGAGGGUGCAGACACUCCCGGGGAACCCCCUGCUGGGCAGGGCUCAGUUACUCAGCUCGUCAAGAAUCUGAGGCAGCUGGACCCUAGGAAGCACCUCUGGGCCCACCCAGGCUUGUCAGGGAGAUGGAGAAUGAAGGGCUUGCUGGCAUUUAUGGGCAAGGCAGGCAUGGCUGAGGGCAAGAUGCCCAUUGGCACGCAGGCAUGAGAACGGAGCCCAGCCCAGAGGGUAUGCUGGGCACCAAGAGGAAACUGGGCAAAAGAGGCCUGGGAUUUGGACCCUGAGAGCCAUAGCACCUCAGGUGCUGGGGUUCAAGAUCUGUAUUGGUCUGGGGGAUCCCAGAUUCCAGGUCCCAGGAUCACAGGAUCAGGCCAGCUGCCCGGAGCUGCAGGCAAGUCCACAUUACAGACUUGCAGCAUCUUGGGGUCUGCCCUGGGGCCCAUCUUUCUGCUGUGACGCUAGAAGCUCAGGGAGGGUGAGACUUGGCCUUGGGCCUUGCUAAGGGUUGCUCCAUGUACAGGAGGCCUUCCAGCCUUAGCAGGUGCUGGGAGCCGCUCUGGGGUCUGAGGAGAUCCCUAUUCCAUCUCCAGGGCAGCUGAUGGUAGCCUCAUCCAGCCUAGGCCAAAUUGGGGGACUCUAGGAGGGAUUCAGGAGAGACAGUUCAUUCCUAAGAAUGGGAAGCAGAGAGAACUCCUAGUGAAAUGGGCUGGGGACACACACUGAGAAGAUGGAGCUUUCUUUUGGGAUGCGUCUCCCUGUUUGGGUGUGUGGGUGUGAAUGGGGUAGCCUCGCCUUGAGGGAAGAUUGCAGAGGAGGAUGUGGUCCUGGAGACUUUCGCUGAAGGGAGAGCCCAGAAUAGGAAGCGCCACCUGCAGACUUGGCUCCAGGGAUUAUAAAUGAGGCUGGUUAAUGAUAUGCCCAGCUGUGAUGGGGCCAGGGAUGGACCCAAAGUAGGAGGAAGUGGGGGCAGAAUACGAGAGAGGAUUCGGAAGCAUUUCCUCCUCAUCGUUCUGGUUAGCUGGAAGGGCUUGAGAUCCUGAUGUGGCCUUAUCUGGGGCUUUCCAGCACUUUCCAGAGCCAGAUGUGGCUCUCUCCUUGCCCAGGUACUGGUCUUGCAGCAGGUCUGGGACAGGACAGGUUUUCCUCAGUGUGAGGGAUUGAGGUUAGAAGAGUGUGUCCCUGAAGCCCGGGUGGGGUAGUCAGUGGUCCCUACCACUGGGGUUUCAGGAAAUAGGUGGGGGAUAGAUGACCCCAGAGACCCCACACCCAGCACUUUCUGCCUCUUUCAAUGCCUACUGUUCUUCUAGCUGCUGCCCUGGCCUCUCGCCACCCUGACAUCAACAACCCUUUGGCAGUGCCCACCUGGGGAGGAGCCCGACCUGGACCCAGGGCAGGGCACAUUAUGCAGGCCCUGCCCCCCAGGCACCUUCUCAGCUGCAUGGGGCUCCAGCCCAUGCCAGCCCCAUGCCCGUUGCAGCCUUUGGAGGAGGCUGGAGGCCCAGGUGGGCAUGGCAACUCGAGAUACACUCUGUGGAGACUGCUGGCCUGGAGUGGGGGCGGCGGGCCCGACGUGGCGUGGAGGUGGCAGCAGGGGCCAGCAGCGGUGGUGAGACACGGCAGCCUGGGAACGGCACCCGGGCAGGUGGCCCAGAGGAGACAGCCGCCCAGUACGCGGUCAUCGCCAUCGUCCCUGUCUUCUGCCUCAUGGGGCUGUUGGGCAUCCUGGUGUGCAACCUCCUCAAGCGGAAGGGCUACCACUGCACGGCGCACAAGGAGGUCGGGCCCGGCCCUGGAGGUGGAGGCAGUGGAAUCAACCCUGCCUACCGGACUGAGGAUGCCAAUGAGGACACCAUUGGGGUCCUGGUGCGCUUGAUCACAGAGAAGAAAGAGAAUGCUGCGGCCCUGGAGGAGCUGCUGAAAGAGUACCACAGCAAACAGCUGGUGCAGACGAGCCACAGGCCUGUGUCCAAGCUGCCGCCAGCGCCCCCGAACGUGCCACACAUCUGCCCGCACCGCCACCAUCUCCACACCGUGCAGGGCCUGGCCUCGCUCUCUGGCCCCUGCUGCUCCCGCUGUAGCCAGAAGAAGUGGCCCGAGGUGCUGCUGUCCCCUGAGGCUGUAGCCGCCACUACUCCUGUUCCCAGCCUUCUGCCUAACCCGACCAGGGUUCCCAAGGCCGGGGCCAAGGCAGGGCGUCAGGGCGAGAUCACCAUCUUGUCUGUGGGCAGGUUCCGCGUGGCUCGAAUUCCUGAGCAGCGGACAAGUUCAAUGGUGUCUGAGGUGAAGACCAUCACGGAGGCUGGGCCCUCGUGGGGUGAUCUCCCUGACUCCCCACAGCCUGGCCUCCCCCCUGAGCAGCAGGCCCUGCUAGGAAGUGGCGGAAGCCGUACAAAGUGGCUGAAGCCCCCAGCAGAGAACAAGGCCGAGGAGAACCGCUAUGUGGUCCGGCUAAGUGAGAGCAACCUGGUCAUCUGAGGGGCGGUCUAGUCUAAGGACACUGCGGCCCUGCCCUGGGAGGUUCCGAAGGCUUCCUGGAGGAGGUGGAGCUGCAGCUGGGACUGUGAGGACCGAGAAGCAAUGGCCCAGCAGACGAGACAGCAAAGACCAAGGCCUGGAGGUGGGAGCGUCUGCCCCAGUGAGGAGGCAGGUGGCCGGCGGGCACUGUGUACAGGAGCAGGCUGAGCCCCGCCCCUGGCCCUGCUGCCAUGUUGCUCCCCUGAAGGAUGCCCCGACCCCCGUGCCUGCCCUGGCUGGAUCCUAGGAGCCCACGGGAUUCUCUGUAUCAUCAGAGGCUGGGCUUGGCAGAGGGGAGGGGCCUGUGCCCGUCACCCCUGGCCCCAUUCCUUGGUAAUUAGCCACACCCUUGCCUCUGUACAGGGCCCUAGAGCAGAUGUGCGUCCCCCUCCUCUUCCAGCAGGUCUAUAAAGGGAAGGGGUAGCAGAAAGUCCUGGGCUAGGAGAGUGAGUCCCUGGGUUCUAAUCUUGGGCACAUCUGUGGCCAUCGCUGGGUCCAUUUUUCUGACUGUGAAGUAAGGAGAGACGUCUCAGUACCCAGGGCCUCUUCAGCUCUUUGUAGGUUCUGGGCUGGGUUGUGGGGGACUGGGGAGCUGGGCUCUACCAUCCCUCCCAUUAGUAGCUUUAUCCAGCCCCGUUUUUGCUGCUUCCAGGGCCUCUGCCUUCAAGGCCCCCAUGGGGCUGUCCAUCCAUGGCUCUGCCUACGGAAGGGGCUUAAUGCAUGUGCCUGCCCCUCCCCCAGCUGUUUUUAAUGAAACUGAAAAAAUAGACUUGAUCCCGGCAGGACUGUGAUACAGAGCCCUAGCCUGCCCAGCCAGCCCCAAGAUCUCAGGAGCUUUAGGGAGAAGACUUGGUGGGGCUGGAGCACACCUUGGGCCUCAGUGGUUUCUGUGUCCCUGUGGUGCCAGUGCUUCUGGGCAGUGCAGGCGGCUGCCAGGCCCAGCCCUGACUUCCACUCUGGCUCAGCAACCUGGUUAUUUAUGUGGGGCCGUGCAGGCAUGGGCCCACUGCCUGUCCAUCCUGUUUCUCUUAUUUAUUGAAACUCACCAUUGCCCUAUCCUUGUGUCUCCACCCCCUUCCAUGUGUUGAAUAAUAAAAGGUGGGAAAGUGCUGUCACGAGGAGCUCCUUUUCUCUGUGCCCUUCCCAGCUUAUCCGCCUGUUCCACUUGUACCUGUCCAGCCCUGCCCUGUGUUGGGCACCGUGACAGGCUGCCCUCCCCUCACAGUUCCUGCACCUCAGCAGCCAGGGAAGCAGGGCCCAGAGGAGACCCAUCAACUCAUCUGGUUCUCACCAAAGCCCCUAGCUAGAGGCAGGGCUGUCCCACAGAAAUAGUGUGAGCCACAUAUGUGACUUUAAAUUUUCUGACAGUCACAUUUCAAAAAGUAAAAAGAAGCAGGUGAACUUAAUUUUUUUUUAACCCAGUCUAUCCAAAAUAUUUUCAUUUCAAUAUAAAAUCAGUAUAAAAAGUGUGAAUGAGCUGUUUUUGCUUUUGCUUUGAAAUCUGGAGUGUAUCUUACACAUCUUGAUUGGAACUCAAAUAUUUCAAGGGCUCCAUAGCCACGUGGCCAGCAGCUACCACACUGGUCAGCGCAGCACCUGAGGAAAUGCACUGUGUGGAGCCCGGGAGGUAAUUGGGGGUGAGGAAGAUGUGCGGGCCAGGGAAUGUGUUCCACAGAGAGGGACAGCAUGUGCAAAGGCUGAGCACCAACACAUAGUGGUCACCUGGGCCUUAUGCCCAGGGAGCCUCCAAAGCAUUCAGCUCCUGCUUGGCCAGUGUGGAGAGGAAAGGAGCCACAGGAGCGGGUGCUACACCCGGCAAGACAGAGCGUCUCCAUCUAAAAUUCCUAGGGCAAGCUUCCAACCCGGCCCAAGGGCCGCAUGUGGCCCAGGAUAUGGCUUUGAAUGGGGCCUAACACAAAUUCAUAAACUUUCUUAAAACAUUGA